ACCCACCUGCUUGGCCCCCACUUCUGAUGCCCGCCUGCUCUGCCUGGCCCGGAGGAGGACCCCAGCUGCGCCAGGGAGGAAGGGGCCGGCUGUGGUGGCUCAUGCCUGUAAUCCAGUGCUGUGGGAGGCCGAGGUGGGAGGAUUGCUCAAGUCCAAGUGUUUGAGGCCAGUCUGGGCAGCAUAGUGAGACCACAUCUCUACAAAAAUCUGCUGUCUGAUCGCCAAGCACCCUCUGCGGGGAGCAGGGUAGGGGGACGUCUUCCUGCAGCUGUGGAAGCUCCAGGACAGGACAGCAGGGGAGAGGGCGUGGGCCUUGCCUCAUGGCGGCAUUGCUAUGGGCAGGUCAUUUGGCCUCGCUGGCCCCUACGGCCUCUACCUCUGUUCACAUCUUGUGAUGGGGUCAAGGUUGCCCUCCCAGAGUAGAAGGACAGGCAAAAGGUGAUGCUGCAAGGAUGGUGCCGAGACAGCAGUGGCACGCUGCAGGCGCUGCCCGGGCCAGGGAACUUAAUGGAGUGGGGACGGACGUGCGGCUCCACUGGUUCCCGGACUCCUGGUCUCCACUGCUGGGCACUCAGGAUCUGCCCGGAGGCCUUGGACACAGGCACCACUGGCAGAGCUUGCCCAUGGCCCUGCUGCCCCACUGCAUGGCUUCGGGCUGCCCCCCGAGGGGUCAGACCUGACGCCCCCACCAUCAGCUUUCCUGUCUGAGGGGCUCCGGGCUGCUUCCCUCCCACCUGGGGCUAGACUGUGUGUGGUUCAGAGGGAGAUGCUGGGUUGGGGGCGCCCACCACACUGGCAUGGGGACCCUGGGCCAGCGGGCCCUACUCUGGGUGGUGGUUUCUCCCCUCUAAGACAAAGAAGAAGUGGGUUGCAAAUCUUUCUGUAAAUAAAAUGCCACAUGGCACCCAAGGAUGUGCCUGGGGGGAGGCUGCCUGUGGUGCAGGUGGGGAGCCAGCCUGCAGCUCCUUCUCUCUCAGCAGAGGCCCGAGGACCCCGGUCAGGGACGGCUCACGCUCUCCUGGACACUGGGGUCAGCUUCUGAGCCUGUGGGCCCAGCCUCGCAUGGCAGGGCUUGGCAGGAGAGAGCUGAGCCUCUGCAGUCAGCCAUUGGGGUUGCUGGAGAUCCAAAGGGGAUCUGCUGUCCCAGGGAUAGAGGCCCCGUGGGGGCAGGGGCUGGGCCCUGUUGGAGUCCUGCUCUACUGGCGUGGCCUCUCCUCCAAAGGAAGUUCCAACGUAAAGCCUGCCCGGGGCCAACUGUAGCAAAGAAGACAGAGGCCGCUGGAGGAAACCCGCUGUAGAGGGCAGGCAGAGGCUGCUCUGUCGGCAGCUGGGAUGUCCCUCAUGACAGCACGCAUGGACGCAGGGUGGAUUUCAGCUGCAUCGGUCCCGGGCCACCCCGCCAGACAUCGCCAAAGGAGGCAACGACAGCAAUCUAAGUGGCCUAGAAGCCACGUCCACACAGGGUCUCCUCUCCCAGUCAAAUCGGACAUGCCCCCAGGGCCUUGGUGCCAAUCACACCUGAGGACGGCCAGCCCUUGGUGUCUGGGUGGCUUUGGAGACAGCAGGCCUGUGGGCUCGGCCGUGUGGAGCAGGUGCACCCAGGGUCUCCACAUCCCUGUCCUGGGAGCGGGUGGGCUGUGUGGCCAGGGGACUGCAAGGCCUCUGCUGAGUCUUUCGGAGUUUCCAGGUCAUCCCCACAAAAGGCCUCUGGAGAAAUGUCUGCAGGUGUGGCCAACCUGAGGUGCCCUGAGUGGGCUCUAGAGGCCACCAUGCAGGAUGUCCAAGGCCCCCGUCCCGGAAGCCCCGGGGAUGCUGAAGACCGGCGGGAGCUGGGCUUGCACAGGGGCGAGGUCAACUUUGGAGGGUCUGGGAAGAAGCGAGGCAAGUUUGUACGGGUGCCGAGCGGAGUGGCCCCGUCUGUGCUCUUUGACCUGCUGCUUGCUGAGUGGCACCUGCCGGCCCCCAACCUGGUGGUGUCCCUGGUGGGUGAGGAGCAGCCUUUCGCCAUGAAGUCCUGGCUGCGGGAUGUGCUGCGCAAGGGGCUGGUGAAGGCGGCUCAGAGCACAGGAGCCUGGAUCCUGACCAGUGCCCUCCGCGUGGGCCUGGCCAGGCAUGUCGGGCAGGCCGUGCGCGACCACUCGCUGGCCAGCACGUCCACCAAGGUCCGUGUGGUUGCUGUCGGCAUGGCCUCGCUGGGCCGCGUCCUGCACCGCCGCAUUCUGGAGGAGGCCCAGGAGGAUUUUCCUGUCCACUACCCUGAGGAUGACGGCGGCAGCCAGGGCCCCCUCUGUUCACUGGACAGCAACCUCUCCCACUUCAUCCUGGUGGAGCCAGGCCCCCCGGGGAAGGGCGAUGGGCUGACGGAGCUGCGGCUGAGGCUGGAGAAGCACAUCUCGGAGCAGAGGGCGGGCUACGGGGGCACUGGCAGCAUCGAGAUCCCUGUCCUCUGCUUGCUGGUCAAUGGUGAUCCCAACACCUUGGAGAGGAUCUCCAGGGCCGUGGAGCAGGCUGCCCCGUGGCUGAUCCUGGUAGGCUCGGGGGGCAUCGCCGAUGUGCUUGCUGCCCUAGUGAACCAGCCCCACCUCCUGGUGCCCAAGGUGGCCGAGAAGCAGUUUAAGGAGAAGUUCCCCAGCAAGCAUUUCUCUUGGGAGGACAUCGUGCGCUGGACCAAGCUGCUGCAGAACAUCACCUCACACCAGCACCUGCUCACCGUGUAUGACUUCGAGCAGGAGGGCUCCGAGGAGCUGGACACGGUCAUCCUGAAGGCGCUGGUGAAAGCCUGCAAGAGCCACAGCCAGGAGCCUCAGGACUAUCUGGAUGAGCUCAAGCUGGCCGUGGCCUGGGACCGCGUGGACAUCGCCAAGAGUGAGAUCUUCAAUGGGGACGUGGAGUGGAAGUCCUGUGACCUGGAGGAGGUGAUGGUGGACGCCCUGGUCAGCAACAAGCCCGAGUUUGUGCGCCUCUUUGUGGACAACGGCGCAGACGUGGCCGACUUCCUGACGUAUGGGCGGCUGCAGGAGCUCUACCGCUCCGUGUCACGCAAGAGCCUGCUCUUCGACCUGCUGCAGCGGAAGCAGGAGGAGGCCCGGCUGACGCUGGCCGGCCUGGGCACCCAGCAGGCCCGGGAGCCACCCGCGGGGCCACCGGCCUUCUCCCUGCACGAGGUCUCCCGCGUACUCAAGGACUUCCUGCAGGACGCCUGCCGAGGCUUCUACCAGGACGGCCGGCCAGGGGACCGCAGGAGGGCGGAGAAGGGCCCGGCCAAGCGGCCCACGGGCCAGAAGUGGCUGCUGGACCUGAACCAGAAGAGCGAGAACCCCUGGCGGGACCUGUUCCUGUGGGCCGUGCUGCAGAACCGCCACGAGAUGGCCACCUACUUCUGGGCCAUGGGCCAGGAAGGUGUGGCAGCCGCACUGGCCGCCUGCAAAAUCCUCAAAGAGAUGUCGCACCUGGAGACGGAGGCCGAGGCGGCCCGAGCCACGCGCGAGGCGAAAUACGAGCGGCUGGCCCUUGACCUCUUCUCCGAGUGCUACAGCAACAGUGAGGCCCGCGCCUUCGCCCUGCUGGUGCGCCGGAACCGCUGCUGGAGCAAGACCACCUGCCUGCACCUGGCCACCGAGGCUGACGCCAAGGCCUUCUUUGCCCACGACGGCGUUCAGGCCUUCCUGACCAGGAUCUGGUGGGGGGACAUGGCCGCAGGCACGCCCAUCCUGCGGCUGCUAGGAGCCUUCCUCUGCCCCGCCCUCGUCUAUACCAACCUCAUCACCUUCAGUGAGGAAGCUCCCCUGAGGACAGGCCUGGAGGACCUGCAGGACCUGGACAGCCUGGACACGGAGAAGAGCCCGCUGUAUGGCCUGCAGAGCCGGGUGGAGGAGCUGGUGGAGGCGCCGAGGGCUCAGGGUGACCGAGGCCCACGUGCUGUCUUCCUGCUCACACGCUGGCGGAAAUUCUGGGGCGCUCCCGUGACUGUGUUCCUGGGGAACGUGGUCAUGUACUUCGCCUUCCUCUUCCUGUUCACCUACGUCCUGCUGGUGGACUUCAGGCCGCCCCCCCAGGGCCCCUCAGGGCCCGAGGUCACCCUCUACUUCUGGGUCUUUACGCUGGUGCUGGAGGAAAUCCGGCAGGGCUUCUUCACAGACGAGGACACACACCUGGUGAAGAAGUUCACACUGUAUGUGGGGGACAACUGGAACAAGUGUGACAUGGUGGCCAUCUUCCUGUUCAUCGUGGGUGUCACCUGCAGGAUGCUGCCGUCGGCGUUUGAGGCUGGCCGCACAGUCCUCGCCAUGGACUUCAUGGUGUUCACGCUGCGGCUGAUCCAUAUCUUUGCCAUACACAAGCAGCUGGGCCCCAAGAUCAUCGUGGUAGAGCGCAUGAUGAAGGACGUCUUCUUCUUCCUCUUCUUUCUGAGCGUGUGGCUCGUGGCCUACGGUGUCACCACCCAGGCGCUGCUGCACCCCCAUGACGGCCGCCUGGAGUGGAUCUUCCGCCGGGUGCUCUACCGGCCCUACCUGCAGAUCUUCGGCCAGAUCCCACUGGACGAGAUUGAUGAAGCCCGUGUGAACUGCUCCACCCACCCACUGCUGCUGGAGGACUCACCAUCCUGCCCCAGCCUCUAUGCCAACUGGCUGGUCAUCCUCCUGCUGGUCACCUUCCUGUUGGUCACCAAUGUGCUGCUCAUGAACCUGCUCAUCGCCAUGUUCAGCUACACGUUCCAGGUGGUGCAGGGCAACGCAGACAUGUUCUGGAAGUUCCAGCGCUACAACCUGAUUGUGGAGUACCACGAGCGCCCCGCCCUGGCCCCGCCCUUCAUCCUGCUCAGCCACCUGAGCCUGACGCUCCGCCGGGUCUUCAAGAAGGAGGCUGAGCACAAGCGGGAGCACCUGGAGAGAGACCUGCCAGACCCCCUGGACCAGAAGGUCGUCACCUGGGAGACAGUCCAGAAGGAGAACUUCCUGAGCAAGAUGGAGAAGCGGAGGAGGGACAGCGAGGGGGAGGUGCUGCGGAAAACCGCCCACAGAGUGGACUUCAUUGCCAAGUACCUCGGGGGUCUGAGAGAGCAAGAAAAGCGCAUCAAGUGUCUGGAGUCACAGAUCAACUACUGCUCGGUGCUCGUGUCCUCCGUGGCUGACGUGCUGGCCCAGGGUGGCGGCCCCCGGAGCUCUCAGCACUGUGGCGAGGGAAGCCAGCUGGUGGCUGCUGACCACAGAGGUGGUUUAGAUGGCUGGGAACAACCCGGGGCUGGCCAGCCUCCCUCGGACACCUGAGCUGCUUGGCCUGCCACGUGUGGGGCCACCUCUCCUCAGCUGGCCACCCUGCACGUUGUGCACUGACCUUUGCCGACCUCCAGCGGAACCCCCCAGGGGGCACCAGCCCCCCAGCAGACAAUGGCCCUCCUGGUGCCUCACCACAGACCCUCACCCAAAGGAACCGCUCCUUGUCCCUCCUGGCCUCCCCGGAGGCACAGCAGUGUCAUGGGGCUGUCUCCCCUGACAGGCACAACUCCCCGGGCAGAAAACGUGCCCCACCGCAUCCCUACCUGGAAACUGACCAGCCUGCACUGUGGAAAAGCUGGCCCUGUGGCGUGACGGGGGAGCACCCCCAUCCAGACUGCGAAGCUGCUCUGGGGUCUGCACCCACCCCUGCCCUGACUUGUGUUGCCUGACAAGAGACUCAUCUUUUUUUGAAA